AUGUUGGAGCAGGGAUCCAGGAUCACUCAAUAAGGGCAGCCUGAGCCUCAAGCUGGAUGCCUGAGAGUGGUAAUCCAGGAACUCAUGCAGCCAGAAUCUGGGGCCAAUGGAACAGUCAUUGCUGAGUUCAUCCUGCUGGGCUUGCUGGAGGCGCCAGGGCUGCAGCCAGUUGUCUUUGUGCUCUUCCUCUUUGCCUACCUGGUCACGGUCAGGGGCAACCUCAGCAUCCUGGCAGCUGUCUUGGUGGAGCCCAAACUCCACACCCCCAUGUACUUCUUCCUGGGGAACCUAUCAGUGCUGGAUGUUGGGUGCAUCAGCGUCACUGUUCCAUCAAUGUUGAGUCGUCUCCUGUCCCGCAAGCGUGCAGUUCCCUGUGGGGCCUGCCUUACCCAGCUCUUCUUCUUCCAUCUGUUCGUUGGAGUGGACUGCUUCCUGCUGACCGCCAUGGCCUAUGACCGAUUCCUGGCCAUCUGCCGGCCCCUCACCUACAGCACCCGCAUGAGUCAGACAGUCCAGAGGAUGUUGGUGGCUGCGUCCUGGGCUUGUGCUUUCACCAACGCACUGACCCACACUGUGGCCAUGUCCACGCUCAACUUCUGUGGCCCCAAUGUGAUCAAUCACUUCUACUGUGACCUCCCACAGCUCUUCCAGCUCUCCUGCUCCAGCACCCAACUCAAUGAGCUGCUGCUUUUUGCUGUGGGUUUUAUAAUGGCAGGUACCCCCAUGGCUCUCAUUGUCAUCUCCUAUAUCCACGUGGCAGCUGCAGUCCUGCGAAUUCGCUCUGUAGAGGGCAGGAAGAAAGCCUUCUCCACAUGUGGCUCCCACCUCACUGUGGUUGCCAUAUUCUAUGGUUCAGGUAUCUUUAACUAUAUGCGACUGGGUUCAACCAAGCUUUCAGACAAGGAUAAAGCUGUUGGAAUUUUCAACACUGUCAUCAAUCCCAUGCUGAACCCAAUCAUCUACAGCUUCAGAAACCCUGAUGUGCAGAGUGCCAUCUGGAGGAUGCUCACAGGGAGGCGGUCACUGGCUUGAGGAGGUCUCAAUUGACCCUUUCUCCCUGUGUCUUGUACUAAAGGAAAAGUCUUCUAGAGCCAGAAACUAGGAAAAAAAUGGUUCACACCUGUUUCUGUUUCAUGGGCAUAAGAAGGACUUUUUGUAGGGAAUAAUAGUUUUCAUUUCUGAAAGCAGCCCUGUCCAAUUAUAAGCAAUGAGUGUAUAGGAUCUGCCAAGCCAGCCCCUUAGACAAAUUCAGCUUCAGGCACCGUGUUCUCUCCUUUCUGGCUAGAGGUGAAACCUAGGAAGCUGUGAGUGCUGACAGGUUCAUGUUCCAGAAGGAAUGACUCUUUGGUUGGUUACAGCCUUAGUUGCCAGAAGUACCCCAGAAAACUCCCCGCCAGAAGUCAUAUUUUUCCCUCAAGUUCAGGUGUGCUUGGUCUGUUUAUAAAACAUAGGUCUAGAGAUUAGGAUUGUUUUAUUUCUCCCAUCAGAACUCUAAAAGCAAAAAUAAAACAAAAAGAAACAAAAACAAAAAAGUAGCUCUUUCUAUUCCCAUUAAACAAGGACCCCAUAGCAUAGACAGGGGACAGAGGGGAAGCUGUAUGAUUAUGUAUUCUCUAGUAAUUCUGGAGCACCUGAUACCUGUGUGCAGCU